GCAGCUCGUCGCCGCCCGCGGGCCUGUCCGACGCCGGGGCCCGGCCCGUCCCCUCCGCCGCCCGGCAGCCAUGUGACCGCGCCGCCGCCCUCCGCGCGCCCGGCCCGCCCGCCGCGCGUCCGCGGCCCGGCCGCAGCCCCAGGCCGCCGAGGGAGCGGCGGGGCCGGCGCCAUGGCCGAGCGAGGCCGCCUCGGCCUCCCCGGCGCGCCCGGCGCGCUCAACACGCCCGUGCCCAUGAACCUGUUCGCCACCUGGGAGGUGGACGGCUCCAGCCCCAGCUGCGUGCCCAGGUUGUGCAGCCUGACUCUGAAGAAGCUGGUGGUCUUCAAGGAGCUGGAGAAGGAGCUGAUCUCCGUGGUGAUCGCUGUCAAGAUGCAGGGCUCCAAACGAAUCCUGCGGUCCCAUGAGAUUGUGCUGCCCCCCAGUGGACAAGUGGAGACAGACCUGGCCCUGACCUUCUCCUUGCAGUAUCCUCACUUCUUGAAGAGGGAAGGCAACAAGCUUCAGAUCAUGCUGCAGCGCAGAAAGCGCUACAAGAACAGAACCAUCCUGGGCUACAAGACGCUGGCCGCGGGCUCCAUCAGCAUGGCUGAGGUGAUGCAACACCCGUCUGAAGGUGGCCAGGUGCUGAGCCUCUGCAGCAGCAUCAAGGAGGCCCCCGUCAAGGCGGCCGAGAUCUGGAUCGCCUCCCUGUCCAGCCAGCCCAUUGACCACGAAGACAGCACCAUGCAGGCCGGCCCCAAGGCCAAGUCCACGGAUAACUACUCCGAGGAGGAGUAUGAGAGCUUCUCCUCCGAGCAGGAGGCCAGUGACGACGCCGUGCAGGGGCAGGACUUGGACGAGGACGACUUUGACGUGGGGAAGCCGAAGAAGCAGCGGAGAUCGAUUGUAAGAACGACGUCCAUGACCAGGCAACAGAACUUCAAGCAGAAAGUGGUAGCGCUGCUGCGGAGGUUCAAAGUGUCCGACGAGGUCCUGGACUCGGAGCAGGACCCUGCGGAGCACAUCCCCGAGGCAGAGGAGGACCUGGACCUCCUGUAUGACACCCUGGACAUGGAGCACCCCAGCGACAGCGGCCCCGACAUGGAGGAUGACGACAGCGUCCUCAGCACCCCCAAGCCGAAGCUGCGGCCAUACUUUGAAGGCCUGUCGCACUCGAGCUCGCAGACGGAGAUUGGGAGCAUCCACAGCGCCCGCAGCCACAAGGAGCCCCCAAGCCCGGCUGACGUGCCCGAGAAGACGCGGUCCCUGGGAGGCAGGCAGCCGAGCGACAGUGUCUCUGACACGGUGGCCCUCCAGGGUGUGCCAGGCCCGAGGGAGCACCCUGGACAGCCUGAGGACAGCCCCGAGGCUGAGGCCUCCACCCUGGAUGUGUUCACGGAGAGGCUGCCGCCCAGCGGGAGGAUCACCAAGACAGAGUCCCUUGUCAUCCCCUCCACCAGGUCCGAGGGGAAGCAGGCUGGCCGACGGGGCCGGAGCACAUCCUUGAAGGAGCGGCAGGCAGCACGGCCCCAGAAUGAGCGGGCCAACAGCCUGGACAACGAGCGCUGCCCGGACGCCCGGAGCCAGCUACAGGUGCAGCUGCAGAUCCCCAGGAAGACUGUGUAUGACCAGCUCAACCACAUCCUCAUCUCCGAUGACCAGCUUCCCGAAAACAUCAUCCUUGUCAACACCUCGGACUGGCAGGGGCAGUUCCUCUCCGACGUCCUGCAGAGGCACACGCUCCCCGUGGUGUGCACGUGCUCUCCUGCGGACGUCCAGGCGGCCUUCAGCACCAUCGUCUCACGGAUACAGAGAUACUGCAACUGCAAUUCCCAGCCCCCGACCCCCGUGAAGAUCGCCGUGGCGGGAGCGCAGCAUUACCUCAGUGCCAUCCUGCGGCUCUUUGUGGAGCAGCUGUCCCACAAGACACCCGACUGGCUCGGCUACAUGCGCUUCCUGGUCAUCCCACUGGGCUCCCACCCCGUGGCCAGGUACCUAGGCUCCGUGGACUACCGCUACAACAACUUCUUCCAGGACCUGGCCUGGAGAGACCUGUUCAACAAGCUGGAGGCCCAGAGUGCGGUACAGGACACGCCAGACAUUGUGUCACGCAUCACGCAGUACAUCGCAGGGGCCAACUGUGCCCACCAGCUCCCCAUCGCAGAGGCCAUGCUGACCUACAAGCAGAAGAGGAAAAAGCAUUUUCAUUUUGACUUUACCCUAAGCCCUGACGAAGAGUCCUCCCAAAAGUUCAUUCCCUUUGUCGGGGUUGUGAAGGUUGGAAUUGUGGAGCCAUCCUCGGCCACAUCAGGCGACUCGGACGACGCGGCCCCCUCGGGCUCUGGCACGCUCUCCUCCACCCCGCCGUCCGCAUCUCCUGCGGCCAAGGAGGCCUCACCCACCCCGCCCUCCUCCCCGUCGGUGAGCGGAGGCCUGUCCUCCCCCAGCCAGGGUGUCGGCGCCGAGCUGAUGGGGCUGCAGGUGGACUACUGGACGGCAGCACAGCCUGCGGACAGGAAGAGGGACGCCGAGAAGAAGGACCUGCCUGUCACCAAAAACACGCUCAAGUGCACUUUCCGGUCCCUCCAGGUCAGCAGGCUGCCCAGCAGCGGCGAGGCUGCAGCCACGCCCACCAUGUCCAUGACCGUGGUCACCAAGGAGAAGAACAAGAAGGUGAUGUUUCUGCCCAAGAAAGCGAAGGACAAGGACGUGGAGUCUAAGAGCCAGUGCAUUGAGGGCAUCAGCCGGCUCAUCUGCACUGCCAGGCAGCAGCAGAACAUGCUGCGGGUCCUCAUCGACGGCGUGGAGUGCAGCGACGUCAAGUUCUUCCAGCUGGCCGCGCAGUGGUCCUCGCACGUGAAGCACUUCCCCAUCUGCAUCUUCGGACACUCCAAGGCCACCUUCUAGCCCCACCCACCAGGGGGCCCACCUCCUGCCCCAUGCUGUGAGGGGCCCAGCUGCAUUUCUGUUAACAUUUCAGUUUACUACAGAGACAGACGCUUAAAACACAAAGAGAAACAGUCUUAAGUAUGAAUGUGCUCACAACGUGGAAACUAACGGGGGAGCUCCUGCCAGGAGCCGAAUAACUGCUCUGCUUAUUAACCCGAACGUUCGGCCCGGGGCUGGGAAGCCAGAAGGACGAUGCUGAGCCAUGGAUCGCGGAAGGCGUCCUCUGGCCUCAGGAGCCACCCAGAGCCUCACAGGCUGAGUUCUUGCCUCUGUGUCCUGUCCUUCCUGGAAGUCAGGACUCUGCUUCCUCAGGGAGCCCGGGGAAGGCGGAGCUCAGUGGCCACAGGCCGAGGGCCAUGGGGCCGCUCAGUCCCGUUGGGGUUGUCCUGAGUUGAGCCUGGGGGGGCCGUCCUGCCCGCCUAAGAGAUGCCCCCAGCACCGCACACUCGUGGUUCCCAAUAAACUCCUGCCUGCGGCGGAGGUUUUAUAGCAGCAGAUAUUUUUAAUGCUUUUCAAUACAUGUUCUAAUGUAGCUGCCAAACAUGUUGCUCUUCUGAAGUCCCCCUGGGGCUGGGCAGAGCCAGCAGAGCCUGCCCCCACUUCCCCAGCCCCUGCCCCACCCCGCCUCACACCUUCCCCACUCUCAGGCUGUUCUUGAAACACCAUGAGGCUUCUGCGUGUAGUCCCUGCCCCAAACUUAGCAAGCACAGGGGCCUCCACAGCCCAGGUGGCCCCAGAAAAUGUUCCAGAGCCCAGCUUGGUACAUAGUGAGAUGCUGCUGGGGUUGGCCUGAGGUGGGGGCCACUUCCUCCACCCCAGUGGGUAUGUCUGAGGUCAGCCAUGGGGAUAUCUGGGUUGAGAUUCAGGUUUUGGUGAAUAUGGGGCAGGCGUCCAGAUGUGUUUGUGUCACCUGCUGCAACGCUGUAGCCAAUGAAGAUUCCAGCGGGAUGGCCUGACCAGCGGGGCCGGCACUUUGGAGCCGUGGGUGCAGCCAGGUACCCCGUGCAGGGCCUGGGAGGCUCUCCAGGCCACAGUCCUCAGAGCGUGUUGGGUCCCAUGUUGUGUGUGGGUUCCAUGCCCUCCACACAGCAGGAGAGGGCUUCCCUGACCACACCUGCCCCCUCAGUCCUGCUUCUCCCCAGUAAGCCUGCACUGUGGGGUCUCCAUAGGAGGAGCUGGGGAAGCUGGGGCCCUCCCAGGGGUCCUGAUCGACCCUGGGGGCUCUUGGCCUGGUUUCGUAAGAUGGAGCACUGCAAAAGGCCAUGCUCAGAAAGCAAACGCAGGGCAGGGUGGGCCUCGAGCCGGGGCUGGAGGGGUCUCCACCCUUGCUGGCCUGAGAGAUGGCCCACAUUUCUUACUUGUGACCGCCCUGCUCUUCCUGGCCGCCCCCCCCAGGUGGCUGAACAGGGUGAUUUUGUUGUGGUGAGGGGCCAGGAUGUGGCCUGGUGUGCAGCCUCAGCUCCCUGGGUUCAGGCCUCAGAGGUAGCCUGUGUGCAGGAGGCAGAGCCCCAGCCCCUCCCAGCCAGAGCCCCUCCACACCAGGGACUCCUCCUUCACCUGGGACCAGGAGCCUGGGGCACACCCCAGGGUGGGGGAGAGGGUAGGAAGGUCUCCCAUUGAAUCCUGGCUUCAGGCUCUGCCCCGAGAAGUGUCUGCGGUGAGGGUGUGAGCCCCGGGCUGAUGGCCUCUGACCCCGGCAACAGGUGGGACCCUGACUGACUCGUUCAGCUGCCCCCAAGCUGGGCUGCAGAGCAUCUGUUUUUCUGCUCUCCAGUUUCUUUUCUUUUUUUUUUUUUUUUUUUUUGAGAUGGAGUCUUGCUCUGUUGCCCAGGCUGGAGUGCAGUGGCAUGAUCUCAGCUCACUGCAGCCUCCGUCUCCCAGGUUCAAGCAGUUCUCCUGCCUCAGCCUCCCGAGUAGCUGGGAUUACAGGCGUGUGCCACCACACCUGGCUAUUUUUUUUGUAUUUUUAGUAGAGAUGGGGUUUUGCCAUGUUGGCCAGGCUGGUCUUGAACUCCUGACCUCAAGUGAUCCACCCGCCUCGGCCUCCCAAAGUGCUGGGAUUACAGGCGUGAGUCACCGCGUCCUGCCUGCUCUUCCUGUUUCUUUCCCAAGGGUCACACUCAGUAGGGAGAUGAAGGUGGAAACAUCCUUGCUGUGGCUUUCUGGCCUCAGAGCAGGUUUUAGAGGAAGGGGCCACAGGCUGCCUAGUGCAUCCUGGCUGUGGGCAGCCCCUUUCCUGGAGCCCUCCUGCCUACCCCGUACCUCCCAUCUGGCUGCACAGCUCCAUCCUUAGCCACGCAAGGGGAGAACAUGGGCAGAGUCUCCAUCCAGCAGCUGGGGGUUCUGGUGGCACUCCCUGUGCCCCUGCUGCUGCUGGGCUGUGGGUCUGCCCUGCACCCAGGAGCCCCACGGUCCAUCCCCCACACCAUGCCCAGCACCAGGGAGGUUGGGCAGACAAGACCUGGGCCAUGCCAGCCCUCUGUGCCUCGGUUUUCCCACUGGUUACACAGGAUGGUCGCAUUUUCCCUGCCUACCUCACAGAGCUGUUCUGAGGGUGCAUGGAGGAGCACUCUGUCCCACCAAGGACAACUAGAAACCAAAGCCAUCUGACAGCCAGUGCGGUAAGGGCGGGGGAUGUGUGUGUGAGGUGUGCACACCCCCCGAGAACCUGGCCCUGGACUGGCCUCACAGGACAGGAGGCAGCCCCUUGUAGAGCUAGGGCUCAGCCCCAUCAGUCUCAAAGGUUAAGCCACCAGUCACCACCGAGGCACCCCUCAGGCCUGGUGGCCACUGUCCACUAUUACGUAGACAGACCCCACCCUCACCCAGGCCAGCUGUGGGCCAGUCCCGCCCUGCAAUCUGGUCUGCUGCCUUCCUCUUCCAUGUUGGUCCCCUUGGCCACUGUCUCUGGGCAUGCAAGCCAGUGUCCUGGUUCAGUGCCUCGGCCAGAGCUGGGGCAGGAGAGGGGCCUCUGGGUGAGAGCUGGGGGUGUCUCUGCAGGGUACUGGCAGCCUUGCCACACUGUCCUCAUUCCCAGAUGGAAAGACCUGAGUGCCUCUCGCCUUCCUCCGGGAAUGAAUUCCUCAUGAAAAUGACCAGGCCACUUCUUCCGAGGGCCAGGCCGCCCCCUCCCCGAGACCUGUCCUGCCGUCCGCGGGUGUGUGGCCUGUAGGGGACUGAGAGCUGGGCUUGCUGGGCACCUCUGGAAUCUGACCCUGUGGGCCAAAGAAGCACCACUGUAGUUUCUGCAGACCCCCAUGCGGUUCAUUGUGCAUUGUUUGGUUUCUAGGAUGUAUGUGUUGCUAGUUUUUUUUAAUGAAACCCUGGAUUAAUGUAAAUAGCUUUUUGGGGAACGGAUUCUAAUGUCACGUAUGUGACCGUGUGGACUAUUUCAAGGUGCUGAUGCAACACUAAUAAACCUGGAGGGGCCGGC